GAGCAAGGACUCGGGGCCCGCGCGGCGCCUCUCGGGGCCGGGCCGCCGCCUCUGCGCUCAGCCCCGCAGGCCGGGCAUGGGUGGGGGCGCCGGGCCGUCACGAUGAGCGCCCUGGGCAGCCCGGUCCGGGCCUACGACUUUCUGCUCAAGUUCCUGCUGGUGGGCGACAGCGACGUGGGCAAGGGCGAGAUCCUGGCGAGCCUGCAGGAUGGCGCGGCCGAGUCCCCGUACGGCCACCCGGCGGGCAUCGACUACAAGACGACCACCAUCCUGCUGGACGGGCGGCGGGUGAAGCUGCAGCUCUGGGAUACUUCAGGCCAGGGAAGAUUUUGUACCAUAUUCCGCUCCUACUCCCGGGGCGCACAGGGUGUGAUCCUGGUCUAUGACAUUGCGAACCGCUGGUCUUUUGACGGCAUUGAUCGAUGGAUUAAGGAGAUCGAUGAGCAUGCCCCCGGAGUCCCCAAGAUCCUGGUGGGGAACCGCCUGCACCUGGCGUUCAAGCGGCAGGUGCCCACGGAGCAGGCCCAGGCCUACGCCGAGCGCCUGGGCGUGACCUUCUUUGAGGUCAGCCCUCUGUGCAAUUUCAACAUCACAGAGUCGUUCACGGAGCUGGCCAGGAUCGUGCUGCUGCGGCAUGGGAUGGACCGGCUCUGGCGGCCGAGCAAGGUGCUGAGCUUGCAAGACCUCUGCUGCCGGGCGGUCGUGUCCUGCACGCCGGUGCACCUGGUGGACAAGCUCCCGCUCCCCAUUGCCUUAAGAAGCCACCUCAAGUCCUUCUCGAUGGCCAACGGCCUGAAUGCCAGGAUGAUGCACGGCGGUUCCUACUCCCUCACCACCAGCUCCACCCACAAAAGGAGCAGCCUCCGCAAAGUGAAGCUCGUCCGCCCCCCCCAGAGCCCCCCCAAAAACUGCACCAGAAACAGCUGCAAAAUUUCUUAAGGAAGGCACUGAAAGAAACACGGCGGAAUCUCUCCAGGAGAAGCUCGGCGUUACCCCCGGCAGCUGGUGGAUGCAUCUCAGAUCCCGGUUCCUCUCGGCGAAUGCUGCUUGCGAAUGUGUGCGACGCCUUCCGUGUGAUGGAAACACACUACCCCGUCGGACUUCGAAUUUCUACGUGGAUGUGCAUGAAGCUCUUGUUUUCGAUGUGUGUUUGUAAAGGGAAAAUUAGUACUCUGCUCGACUCUUGGUAACAUGAAAUUCUGAAUGUUACUUUAUCAUGAUUGCACUGCAACUUUUUCCUUAAAAUAACUGCUUUUGUAAGAACGGUGAUAUUGGAGUGAUUAGUAUAAAUUCAAUGGAAUUUGAGAAGCAAUGGCAGCGGGAUAAUUUAGAGUCACUGAUAUUACGAGAGGGGUCUUUUUGUAAACCUCCUUUUCAAUGUCAAAGCGCCAAUUUAUAAAACGCUGCAGAUGUAGAGGUUAUGUGCAACUGAUCUGUCCAGUUUGUGUAUGAAAUGGAUUUGAUAAAGUUUUUGCUAGUUAUUUACUACAUUUUGGGAUUAAUAAGUGAUUUAUAUGCAUAUUUUUCUGUAAAUCUACAGUUUUUUGUACAAGAUAUUCUACAAGUUAUGAAGCUAAGGGAAGAAAAUGCCAAAGAUACCUCUAGUUAUGUUGAACACAGCCAGCACAGUUUCGACAUGUCAAGGAAGAGCUGUUUCAGUAAAGAAUGAAGUGAAAACACUUAUUUAGGAAAAUGUUUCUCAACAAUAAAAUGUAUAGUUGUUUCUCUCUUGGUAGAGUUGGCGACCGGUUCUUUCGAAUUUUGUAUUUAUUUAUUUAUUUAUUUUUGAGACAGAGUUUCGCUCUUGUUGCCCAGGGUGGAGUACAAUGGCACGAUCUGGGCUCACCACAACCUCCGCCUCCCGGGUUCAAGCGAUUCUCCUGCCUCAGCCUCCCGAGUAGCUGGGAUUACAGAGGUGCACCACCACGCCCGGCUAAUUUUUGUAUUUUUAGUAGAGAUGGGGUUUCACCAUGUUGGUCAGGCUGGUGUUGAACUCCUAACCUCAGGUGAUCCACCCACCUUGGCCUCCCAAAGUGCUGGGAUUACAGGCGUGAGCCACUGCGCCCGGCCAGAUUUUGUGUAUUUCUUAUAGCCCUUUACUUCACUGCGCCACUGCCUGGUGUAGACAUCACAUAUCGGAGCUAAUACACGACACUGGCAACAAGGCUGAAUCCUUGAACUGUUGUCGCCUGUUGAGAAAGGAUUCCUUUUCCGGAACAGAAGUGCAGAGGAGGAGAGAGCGGAGAGUUAAAAGCUGGCACCCAGGCAUGUGCCUGUCUGAGAAAUCAGAGCCGUGCUCCUGAGCCUCGGUGAGGAGCUCCGAGGGGCUGUCAGGAAUUCCGCAUGAAGAUGUAGCCCCUGACCCCGACUGCCUCAGAGCAGGGCUGACCGCAAAGACCUCCAGGGCCGCUCUCUUCCCUGGUCACACUGUUGAACGUUUCUCUGUGGCUGGGGGUCGCAAAUGAGGGACUAAACCAAAAAAACGAAGCGAGAAAAUACCCAGAUGUUCCUAGUUCCUGCUGAUGAUCUGUAGAUUCUUAGAAACUUAAGGGACCCAGCUGGGUGUGAUGGCUCACACCUGUAAUCCCAGCACUUCAGGAGGCCGAGGCAGCCGGAUCAGAGGUCAGGAGUUCAAGACCAGUCUGGCCAACGUGAUGAAACCCCGUCUCUAAUAAAAUUACAAAAAUUGGCUUGGCAUGGCAGCGCACACCUGUAAUCCCAGCUACUCAGGAGGCUGAAGCAGGAGAAUCACUUGAACCUGGGAGGCAGGGGUUGCAGUGAGCCGAGAUCGUACCACUGCACCCCAGCCUGGGCGACAAGUGAAACUCCAUCUAAAAAAAAAAAAAAAAAAGAAAUUUAAGGGACCCUAGAAUCAGGGGCAAAGCCUGUAUUCAGAGAUGGUGGAACCGAGGCCCAGACAGGAGAGAGGAGCACUGGUCCCUGCGGGUGGACCCAGGCUUGGGGGUGUCUGGCCACCUGGGCACGGCAGCCACGGGGACAAAGUCCACGGGGAGGCAGGGGUGUGGUCUGUGGGCAGAAGGUGAACCCUGAGGGGACAGUGUCUGGAGAGGGUGGCCAGCCUCGUGCAGGCACGCUGCAAAGACCUGUGCACCCUUCUCUCUGCUGUGCCACAGGUGGGGUGAGAACGACAGGGCCGACCUCCCAGCUGCAAACACAAGGACACUGAGAUGCACAGAAAGGAGAGUCCACGUUGAAGAAACCCACGUUGAGGGGCCUCUUCUCCCUCCGUUCCCAGCUCGCUGAUGGUGAAGGGUAAGGAAAUGGAUCCUCCCAUUGCAACAUUAAACCAGGCCAAACCUGUAUUUUUCUCUUCCUUCCUUUUUCUUGUUUUGUAAUUGAUGUCUCCUCGGGACUACUGAUAAUGUCCUAGAAAGAAUAAAAUAAAGUUUCCCAAGGCUUUGUGACUCAGAGCUCUUUGGAGGUGUUCACCGAAUGCACGGGCCGCCCGGAGGCCUUGGCCCUCCAGGGAAACACCACCAGAAGUCCCCAGAAGCGGAACAUGUAGCAAGGAGGCUCCCCGAGAUCUCCCAGAGGGAGCACAGCCCUGCCAAGUUAUUGGUUUUGGACUUCCGGCUUCCAGAGCUACGAGAAAAUAAAUAUUUGUUAUUUAAGUCACCAGGUUUGUGGCGAUUGUUACGGCAGCCUCAGGAAACUCCUACAAGGAAGUGAGUUACGCUCACGGCAGAAAGUGCUACAGCAAACCAAGGCAGAACAAAAACAGACGAAACCUAAUACAGACCGGACUAAGUAGAAGACUGUGUGUUUGGGUGGUGAAUAUACAAAAAACAUAAAUAUAAAUUAAACCUUA